ACAAUGCAGCGCGGCGCGCUGUCCCCGGUGCUGAUGCUCAGCGCUGCCCCGGAGCCUCCGCCGCGCCCGCCUCCCGCCCUCUCCCCACCGGGCUCGGGCCCAGGCUCGGGCUCCCGCCAUGGCUCGGCUCGUCCCGGUCCUACCCCAGAGCCGUCGGGGAGCCUGGGCGCGGCGCUCGACAGCAGCCUGCGUGCCGCCGUGGCGUUCAAGGCAGAGGGCCAGCGCUGCUAUCGAGAGAAGAAGUUCCGGGAGGCCAUCGGCAAGUACCACCGAGCGCUGCUGCAGCUGAAGGCGGCGCAGGGGGCCCGCCCUAGCGGCCUGCCCGCCCCCGCCCCCGGGCCCACCAGCAGCCCCGGGCCGGCGCGCCUCAGCGAGGAGCAGCGGCGCCUGGUGGAGAGCACGGAGGUGGAGUGUUACGACUCCCUCACGGCUUGCCUGCUGCAGUCGGAGCUGGUAAACUACGAGCGCGUGCGCGAGUACUGUCUCAAGGUACUGGAGAAGCAGCAGGGCAACUUCAAGGCCACCUACCGUGCCGGCAUUGCCUUCUACCACCUGGGCGACUACGCACGCGCGCUGCGCUACCUGCAGGAGGCCCGCAGCCGGGAACCCACAGUGGCUCGGAGAGAACAGACUUCUUGCAGAUGUCGCUGGAGGAUGAGAAGUGUGACGGGAGCCUCUGCGAAGAGGCAUUCCUGGCAGAGGGUGCCGCAAAUACAGGCGCACAGAGGUGUGCGAUGGCUCCGCUGUGACUGGGGACUGCCGACUGUGACUGGGGCUUUGGGGAAGGGCUCUGGCUCUACUGGCUGUGUGAGCGAGCUGCUGGAUACUUCGGAGAAUGGGGUGUGAGCCAGGGAGGUGUGGAAGUCACCUGCUGCCCCGGGACACCCAGAUGAUGCCCUGCCCACCUCCCCUGCAGACACCAAUGUGCUCCGCUACAUCCAGCUGACUCAGCUGAAGAUGAAUCGUUGCAGCCUCCAGCGGGAAGACAGUGGGGCUGGGUCCCAGACUCGGGAUGUAAUUGGCUGAGGCCAAUCCAGGGGGACCUCUCUAUCCCUCGCCCUCCCACCUCACCAUGUAACUUCCCCCGACUCAUGUGUUUGUUGGUAAAACACUUGUCACUGGUGAUCAUAA